AGUCGGCGCCAGCGGCCGCACGCCGCGGAGCAGGGGCUCGGAGGUCCCGGGAUUACGGUGCUCGAGCACGCUGGUGGGAAAGGACCCGGGACUUGAACAGUGUUGUGCGGCGCCAUGCAGGUCUCCAGCCUCAAUGAGGUGAAGAUUUACAGCCUCAGCUGCGGCAAGUCCCUUCCUGAGUGGCUUUCUGAUAGGAAGAAGAGAGCGCUACAGAAGAAAGAUGUAGAUGUCCGUAGGAGAAUUGAACUUAUUCAGGACUUUGAAAUGCCUACUGUGUGUACCACUAUUAAGGUGUCAAAAGAUGGACAGUACAUUUUAGCAACUGGAACAUAUAAACCUCGGGUUCGAUGUUAUGACACCUAUCAAUUAUCCUUGAAGUUUGAAAGGUGUUUAGAUUCAGAAGUUGUCACCUUUGAAAUUUUGUCUGAUGACUACUCAAAGAUUGUCUUCUUACAUAAUGAUAGAUACAUUGAAUUUCAUUCGCAAUCAGGUUUUUACUACAAAACCAGAAUACCAAAGUUUGGGAGAGAUUUCUCUUACCACUAUCCAUCCUGUGACUUGUACUUUGUUGGUGCAAGUUCUGAAGUUUAUAGGUUAAACUUAGAACAAGGACGAUACCUGAAUCCUCUACAAACUGAUGCUGCGGAGAAUAAUGUUUGUGACAUAAAUUCAGUGCAUGGCUUGUUUGCCACAGGAACCAUAGAGGGUAGAGUGGAGUGCUGGGACCCAAGAACUCGAAACAGAGUUGGCCUGUUAGACUGCGCCUUAAACAGUGUCACAGCAGAUUCAGAGAUAAACAGUUUACCAACAAUCUCUGCUUUGAAAUUUAAUGGUGCCUUGACCAUGGCAGUUGGAACAACCACAGGGCAGGUUUUAUUAUAUGACCUUCGAUCUGAUAAGCCAUUGCUAGUUAAAGAUCACCAGUAUGGGCUGCCCAUUAAGUCCGUUCAUUUCCAGGAUUCAUUAGAUCUGAUUUUGUCUGCUGACUCUCGAAUUGUCAAGAUGUGGAAUAAGAACUCCGGAAAAAUAUUUACUUCCUUGGAGCCAGAGCAUGACCUUAAUGAUGUUUGUCUCUACCCCAACUCAGGCAUGCUUCUGACGGCCAAUGAAACCCCCAAGAUGGGCAUCUAUUACAUUCCAGUUUUGGGUCCUGCUCCUCGGUGGUGUUCCUUCUUAGACAACUUGACCGAAGAAUUAGAAGAGAAUCCAGAAAGCACAGUCUAUGAUGAUUAUAAAUUUGUCACCAAGAAAGACCUUGAAAAUUUAGGGCUCACCCACCUCAUUGGAUCUCCUUUCCUCCGGGCAUAUAUGCAUGGGUUUUUCAUGGAUAUAAGACUCUAUCACAAGGUGAAACUGAUGGUAAAUCCAUUUGCUUAUGAAGAAUAUAGGAAAGAUAAAAUACGACAGAAAAUAGAAGAAACACGUGCACAGAGAGUCCAGUUAAAGAAAUUGCCAAAAGUUAACAAAGAGCUGGCACUUAAAUUAAUUGAGGAAGAAGAGGAGAAGCAGAAAUCUACAUGGAAAAAGAAAGUUAAGAGUCUUCCUAAUAUUCUCACCGAUGAUCGAUUUAAAGUUAUGUUUGAGAACCCUGACUUCCAAGUAGAUGAAGAGAGUGAAGAAUUUAGGCUUCUGAAUCCACUUGUUUCAAAAAUUAGUGAAAAAAGGAAGAAGAAACUAAGACUCUUAGAGCAACAAGAACUUCGUGAAAAAGAAGAGGAGGAAGAGCCGGAAGGAAAACCAAGUGAUGCAGAAAGUUCGGAGAGUUCAGAUGAUGAAAAAGCCUGGGUUGAAGAGGUCAGGAAGCAACGCAGACUCCUCCAGCAGGAGGAAAAAGUGAAGCGGCAGGAACGACUCAAGGAGGACCAGCAGACAGUCCUAAAGCCCCAGUUUUAUGAGAUCAAAGCAGGAGAAGAAUUUAGAAGCUUCAAAGAUUCUGCCACAAAGCAGAAACUGAUGAACAAAACCCUUGAAGAUCGUUUGAAAAUUGAAGCAAAAAAUGGGACAUUGAGUGUAUCCGACACCACCGUUGGCAGCAAACAAUUGACAUUCACGUUAAAGAGGUCUGAACAGCAGAAGAAGCAACAGGAGGCUGAGAAACUGCAUCGACAAGAAAGGAAAAGACUCCGUCGUUCGGCCGGACACCUGAAGUCAAGACACAAAAGAGGACGGUCGUUUCAUUGAUUUGGGAAGUGGUCCUACCUGUGAUUAGGGAGGGGUACGUCUCCCCCAAACUGAUCAUCGUUAGGGUGUUAAACACAGACGAGGAAACACACGUUUUUAAAGUUCAUGUACGUUCUUGUACACAGAGGUAAAGAUUUGAAAACCUGUGCCUUGUGGGUUGGACUUUGAAGCUGGCCCCGCCGACGGCCACCGCACAGCCCCAGGGGUGUGCUUGCGAGUCGUUGCUCCCUGGAAACAUUGUCCUUUCCCCACGGCGUUAAUCAUGAAAACCAGGCUGGGGUUUUUUUAAUAUUGUGAAAUGUACACCAUGAAAUGAAAGGUUUAUCCUGUGCCAGAAACCAAGGUUUAUCAUGCUCUAGGAACUUUUUUCUUACACUGCCUACCGCCAUUCAUGAUUAAACCAUCCAGAAAUACCAUCCCUGUUUUACCUGGUGUCUGUGUAUUGCCUGUGUUUGUGUUUAUAAGUUUAUGCUGAUAGGUUUGUUCGGCUUGUUUAUGUAUUAGUUUGGGAUUUGUUUUUAAAUAAUUUAUACCAAGAGAGUAUAAUCUAAUGGUGCAGGUUGAGAGCAUCCCAAAUCCGAAAAUCUAAAACUGUUUGAGCACUGUAUUUAUCUGUUCUUGCACUGCUAUAAAGAACUACCUGAAACUGGGUAAUUUAUAAGUAAAGAAAAGAGGUUUAAUUGACUCACAGUUCUACAGGUGGUACAGGAAGCAUGGCUGUGGAGGCCCUGGGAAGCUUACAAUCGUGGCAGAAGGUGAAGCGGAAGCAGGUAUGUCCUGCGUGGCUAGAGCCAGAGGAGGAGGGCAAAGGGGCAGAUGCUGCACACUUUCAAACACCAGAUCUCCAAGAACUCACUAACACAGAAUAGCAAGGGGGAAGUCUGCCCCCAUGUUUCAGUCACCUCCCUCCAGGCCCCUCCUCCAACACCGAAGAUUACAAUUUGACAUGAGAUUUGUGUGGGGACACAGAGCAAAACCAUAUCAAGCACUGACAUGACAUUGGAGGAAAAUGCUCAUUAGAGCUUUUCAGGUUUUGGAUUUUCAGAUUUGGGAUACUUGACUAGUAAAUAUAAUACAGAUAUUCCAAAACACACAAAAAAACCAAAGUCUAAAAGACUUCUGGUCCCAAGCAUUUCAGAUAAGGGAUACCCAACCUGUAAUAAUGGGAAACAAGCAGUAGAGGCUGUUGGUUAAUCUUGGCACAAGUUUAAUUACAGGUUUUUUUUUUUUCCUGUUUCUUAAGUACAGUCAAACAUAAACUUACUGGAGGAAACAUUUAUAAAAAUAAAUAUACUUUCAUUUGAAUAGCUUCUUUGA